CUCGUCUGCUUCCGGCCCUGUGGCCUGGUGGGGCUCUGCAGGCUCCCUCGGGAGUGGUCCUUGGGCCGUGGCCCCUCUGGGGUGAGCGUGGAUGAUUAGUACCCAGAAGGGACUGUGUCCAAAAGGAGCCGGCCAGAAACGGGUUGCGGACACGGCUGGGCUGACAGAAGGCAGCCCCCACGAGGCCUUUGGCUCUGAGGACCCUGGGUCAGAGCGACUUCUCCAGCCUGCGCAGGGGGUGUUAGUCUUACCCAGAGGGUCCAGAGCUGCCGUUCAACAGGAUGUCCCAGAUUCUCAGAUAGGGCCCAACUACCCUAAGCAUACCUAGCAAGGGCAGGCUGCGGCAUGGAAGUACUGGGCUAGGCGUUUGGGUGACCUGGGUCAUAAUCCUGGCUCGGAAAGGGCGCGUACCCUUUGGCGAGGGAUGCGGGCUGGUACCGUGAGGUUUAAGAAGCAGAAAACAUGACAGCCUCUUUAAGUAGCCCUGGGUACGUCACUUGACCCCAGUGAGCCUCAGUUUCCAUAUCCAUAAAAUGGCGAUGGUAAUUAUACUAGCCUCACAGUGUCUGAUGAGAUCUCUGGAGCCUAUUUAUCUCACGGGAAAAUUUUUGAAGAGUGAAACUAGUUGAUCUAGGCCUGAGGGAGCUCAAUCCUGGUAGCAACACCCCUGAAUUCCUGGUGGUGAAAGGAUGUGGCCCCAGGACCCAUCCCGGAAGGAGGUGCUGAGGUUUGCAGUCAGCUGCCGUAUCCUGACUCUGAUGCUGCAGGCCCUCUUCAAUGCCAUCAUCCCAGAUCACCAUGCAGAAGCCUUCUCUCCUCCUCGCCUGGCCCCCUCAGGCUUUGUGGACCAACUCGUGGAAGGUCUUCUGGGCGGCCUGUCUCACUGGGAUGCUGAACACUUCUUGUUCAUUGCUGAGCAUGGCUACCUGUAUGAGCACAACUUUGCCUUCUUUCCUGGUUUCCCCUUGGCCCUGCUGGUGGGGACUGAACUGUUGAGACCCUUACGGGGGUUACUGAGUCUACGCAGUUGCCUGCUGAUUUCGGUAGCAUCACUCAAUUUCUUGUUCUUCAUGUUGGCUGCAGUUGCACUUCAUGACCUGGGUUGUCUGGUUUUGCACUGUCCCCACCAGUCCUUUUAUGCAGCUCUGCUUUUCUGUCUCAGCCCUGCCAAUGUCUUCCUGGCAGCUGGUUACUCAGAAGCUUUGUUUGCCCUCCUGACAUUCAGUGCCAUGGGGCAGCUGGAGAGGGGCCGAGUCUGGACUAGUGUACUCCUCUUUGCCUUUGCCACUGGGGUACGCUCCAACGGGCUGGUCAGUGUUGGCUUCCUCAUGCAUUCUCAAUGCCAAGGCUUUUUCUCUUCUCUAACGAUGCUGAAUCCUCUGAGACAGCUCUUUAAGCUGAUGGCCUCUCUGUUUCUGUCGGUGUUCACACUUGGCCUUCCCUUUGCCCUCUUUCAGUAUUAUGCCUACACCCAAUUCUGUCUGCCAGGCUCAGCCCGCCCCAUUCCUGAGCCUUUGGUACAGUUAGCUGUAGACAAGGGCUACCGGAUUGCAGAGGGAAAUGAACCGCCUUGGUGCUUCUGGGAUGUUCCACUAAUAUACAGCUAUAUCCAGGAUGUCUACUGGAAUGUUGGCUUUUUGAAAUACUAUGAGCUCAAGCAGGUGCCCAAUUUUCUACUGGCUGCACCAGUGGCUAUACUGGUUGCCUGGGCAACUUGGACAUACGUGACCACUCACCCUUGGCUCUGCCUUACACUUGGGCUGCAAAGGAGCAAGAACAAUAAGACCCUAGAGAAGCCCGAUCUUGGAUUCCUCAGUCCUCAGGUGUUUGUGUACGUGGUCCACGCUGCAGUGCUGCUGCUGUUUGGAGGUCUGUGCAUGCAUGUUCAGGUUCUCACCAGGUUUUUGGGCUCCUCCACUCCUAUUAUGUACUGGUUUCCAGCUCACUUGCUUCAGGAUCAAGAGCCGCUGUUGAGAUCCUUAAAGACUGUGCCUUGGAAGCCUCUUGCAGAGGACUCCCCACCAGGACAAAAGGUCCCCAGAAAUCCUAUCAUGGGACUUUUGUAUCACUGGAAAACCUGUUCUCCAGUCACACGAUACAUUCUAGGCUACUUCCUGACUUACUGGCUCCUGGGACUACUCCUACAUUGCAACUUCCUGCCUUGGACAUGACCUGGACUCUCCAGGGACAGGUUGGAAGCCAACUUAACCCAGGGGUCUGAAAGUAAAAAUACACAUUGGAACUGCCUCUGCUGCCCUGGGAUCAUUACUGUGUCCAUUAUAAUCUUUCUCUUUCUCUUUGAAAGCUGGUCAGGAAUGGGAGAAGUGUCAGACACUAGAGAGCCCCUUCUGGUCCUGGCUAGGGCAAAUUUUAGACAACUAUUUUCUCUGUAAGUGAAGAUUGUCGUAUUCCAAGUCUAAAAUACACCUGGAUCUGUCUAGUCAAUCAACAUAGCAGAGACAGUCUUAAACCUACCAUUGACCUGUGUGUAAAUUUAAAUGUCAAUUUAUUGAAGUGUAAAUUUCAUCAAAGGCAUUAGCUGACAGGCUGGUAACAGUCCACACAAGAUGGUAUAGGCCUGAACAGUGUAGUGGCAGUAAUAAAGUGGGACCAUUUUUUCCAAAUGCGACAUUGUUUCUGAUGUUUUUUUUUAUGAUUUGUGCAUGUAUUUUUAUAUGAAAAAAACUUACAAAGAUAUGCAAAUUAAACUUCUUUCAGUUAUACAUGCAAUGAAUUGCCUUUUUAAAAAUAAUACAGGCCAGGCACGACGUUUCACACUGUAAUCCCAGCACUUUGUGAUGCCGAGGUGGGCAGAUCACUUGAGGCCAGGAGUUUGAGACCGGCCUGGCCAACAUGGCAAAACCCCGUCUCUACUAAAAAUACAAAAAUUAGCCGUGCAUGAUGGUACACACCUGUAAUCCUACUCGGGAGGCUGAGGCAUGAGAAUUGCUUGAACUUGGAAGGCGGAGGUUUCAGUGAGCUGAGUUUGCGCCACUGCGCUCCAGCCUGGGCAACAGAGUGAGGCUCUGUCUCAAAAAAAGUAAAAAAUAAAAAUAAUACAAAUCUUUCCAUGUGGCAAAAAGUAAAAUAAUUUUAAAAAGUUAAAAUAAUAUAAAUCAGCUGGGGGAAAAAAGGGUAAGAAGAAGGCAUCAGGAACCCUGGAUUCUAGUCCUCUCAGUAAAACCCCAUUUACCAGCCAUGUGACUUGGGAGAGUUUUCAGAACCUUAGUUACCACCUCUGAAACCAUGGGAAAUGAUGAUAUUCUUCAGGGGGUGGUGGUGAAUGAUGCAGUCUCUUGUAGGUCCCUUUCUGCUCUAACAUCUUAAGAACUGCCUUAAACAACAGAAUCACCCCAGUCUAAAUGCUAAUGUAGAGGCUUAAAUGUGUGAUUUUAGGAGAAAAUAUCCAGUUCUCCUGUUUUCAGCAAUUAGAAGAAACUCCUCCUCCACCGAGUGCAACUCUUGGGAGUAAUUUAGGUGGUCUUUCCUUUCAAUGAGGGAAAGCAGUAACAUCUGGCAGAUAAGGUGCCUGUUGUGCCGUUCUCAGAUGCCUGCUUACUUGAUCAGUAGACAUGGGUCAGAGGCGCCAACACGGCGGCAGGAAUUGGUAAAUUGUACGUAAGUCCAAGGUGGAAUGAAAUGGUAUCUGCCCUGCUUCCUGGCCCCCGUUUGGUCAUGAGCCUAUCACUAUAAUGGUAGUAAGAUCACUGGCCCCUGCUGAGCUACUUUUGCCCAUUCCUUGAGCCAGACGAGAGUUUGGCUCUGUAUCAUCCAUCACCUCUUUUAUUUCCCAUUUAAGCCAAAACAUCCAGUAAGCAGAAACUCUUCAAAACAGAUGGGUAAUCAUAAGCAGCUUCUGGAAAGCCUCAAGAAUUGGAAUUUUGACACACUCCCUCUGACCAUGACAGAAAGCUCAACUUGCCAGCUGAAGGGAAGCUCCUGGCUGAGCCCCAGCACCCUCUGUUGGAGCUUCUGGUCAGCCUGGCCAAUAAGCAUUUCCCAUCCAUCGCCCCAGCACUAGGACAGCUGAGAGAAUUUGGUUCAGAGUCAAAUGCUUCUGAAAAUGUACACACAGAUCAGGGCAGCCCUCUGCCUUCUGCCAAGACACCAAGUGCCCUUCUUGGCAAACGAUGAUCACCCCUGCCCUAGUGUCCCUCCAGUUAGUUGGCAGAAACUGUUCCCUUUCUCCUUGCCAACAGCUGCAAAUCCAGAGACUUCCACCUUGCGUGCAGGAAGUGUUGGGGUCCUGUUUCAGCUCUUUAUUGCCGAGGUAGGAGCACUGGGUUCUUCGCUCUCCUCUUUGCCUCCUUUUGGGGGAUAAUCAGGACUGAUUAUUCCUCUACUGGAAGAGGUGACUCAGACCCCACAGAGUAGGUGUGAUGUCACUGCUCUGGCAGUCUCAGUUUAACCUUCACACUAGAUCUCAUCAUGCCCAGAAACCUUGUAACAGGAGCCCAGCUAGGUGGGUGCACCUGGCAUGAGCUGGACAAGGUUUUCUCUCUGACCUUGCAGGGAUUUAGUUGUUCUCUAAGGAGCUAAGGAAUGGGCUGAUUUUAUGACCAGCAGCUGUCCUUUUACCAUCCUAUUAACAGUCUCUUUAAUAGUCUGGGAGAGGGACAUGAAGGACCCAAGGCAGGAAGUUUCCUGUUUACCCUGAGGCCUAACAAUGCCACAGCUAGGUGGGGUGUCUACAGUUUCAGAGAAAAGUCAUUUCCUUCUGAGACCCUGCUAAAACAGAAACCAGACGCCUCAGCCUCACGUACCUAGAAGUAGAUGCUUUUUUUUGUUCUUUAAUGAAGGUGGGAGGAGAGUGUUUGACAUACCUUUACCAGUCCUCCUGGAAAAAUGUUACUUUUAUUGAAUAGACCCUCUCACUGUCAUCUGAAAAUGUAAUAUGUGCAGGCUCAAGGGAUUUGAAACUGAUUGAUUCUUUCAGUAAUUGUUUAUUAAUGCCUAUUUUAGGGGAAUAAAGAUGACUCAGCUAUG